AGCACACUAGAGGAAGUCGUGCUACCCCCGCGGAGUUGUCGUGUGUUCUGGAUUCAUUCCGGCACCACCAUGUCGAAGGUUUCCUUUAAGAUCACGCUGACGUCGGACCCACGGCUGCCGUACAAAGUGUGAGUAGCUCGGCCGAGAUGGGCCUUUUGGGGCCGGACAAGACGGGGCUGGGUUGGGGAUGAUCCGAGCUUUUCCAACAACUACCCCACGCAGUCUUCAUCUCUUCACUUCAUCUACUUUCCUGGCUCGCGCCCUUCCAGGAGCCUUUCCCACCGGAGCCUGCGAGGAGAGACUCAGUGUUCCUGAAAGUACACCUUUCACAGCAGUCUUAAAGUUUGCAGCAGAAGAAUUUAAAGUUCCUGCUGCAACAAGUGCAAUUAUUACCAAUGAUGGAAUAGGAAUAAAUCCUGCACAGACUGCUGGAAAUGUUUUUCUAAAACAUGGUUCAGAACUGCGGAUUAUUCCUAGAGAUCGUGUUGGAAGUUGUUAAUAUCUGCUACUUGGAACAUACGAUUGCCUUUCAGAAUAAAUAUUGGUAUUUUUUGUUGUUGUAAAAUUGAAAUCAGGCAUUUAACAUACUAUGAAAACACCAGGAGUCAAUGAUUAAUGAAAGGUGACUCAUCUGUCCCUUUUUGUUGUCCAUACUCUUCCUAUGAAGAGGGAAUGCGUAUGAAUUAAGGCUACUACUGUCACAGAAGAUCAUAGUCUUUGAUGCUACCUCACAACACAAACAGGUAGUUCGUUGGGGGCAAAUGAAUUAGCCAACUGUUAACUGGAAGCUUUUGAUAAUUUUUUUUUUUAGAACAAUUUGGAACAUUAAAAUUUACUGAAUCGUAUAUAUUCAUCUGAGAUAAAAAUAUAAAAAGAAUUAUGGACCCUGGAUGGCAAUUUGCUUGAUAGCAUCUGAUUUGCAGACUCAUAAUUUGAUUUUUAAUUAAAUAUAUAGGUUGUGAUGAAGUGAAUAGACAUAUCAGUGAACAGUUAACUAUAUUAAAUUUUUAUCAUUUACUUUUUUUAAGAUUCAGACCUCAGUUAUAUAAAUUUCAGUUUAAUAUCAACCAAAAAAUUAAAAUUUUAAUCUAACCCUUAUGUGUAUAAAUUGGUGUCCCAUACCAGCUUUUAAUGGUGGACCUAUAGAAUCCAGUACUUUUAAUGGUGGGAAUUUACAGUAGAAGCAUCCUUUGCUGAGUUAUACAUUCCUUUAUCAAUCUCUUUUGAUACAACAUUUAAAACAAGUAGCUUCAAGAAACCACUGGUGUUUUGAGGAUAGUAUUUCUAAAUAGCAUUCAGGAACAGAGUAUUAUUGCACAGAUCUGAAGAUCAAAAAAAAGCUCAAGGAAAUACAGAUCGGAAGUGCUGAUGAGUUAUAUUUAUUGAAAACCCAACUUUUAAGGAAGUGCUAAGAUCAGUCACCCAUGUGAAUAAGAAGCCAGGAAAGGAAAGAUGGGGAAGCCCAGAUCACCAGGCUUCUAUUAAGGAGGAAAGCAACAGAGGAAACAGUGAAGGGGAACAGAAGGGGGUAGCAAAGUGUUACAGAAAAGCGGACUGGAUAGACAAAACUGCAGAAGGUGUAUGUUGGGGAGAACUGAAAGGGAAAACAAAAUACUUGACAUAGUCUUAAGUAGAAGAAGGCAGUUAGAGAAAACAAAGUAUCUACUGGCCUUGUCAACAUACAGACUUCAAAAUACCCCUUAUGAGAAUCCAAAGAAUGAUGUGUGUAAGGGAAGAUUUUAUUUGCCCUUCCGGAAGAAAUCAGUAUCUAUGCAAAUCUUGAAAGACGAAAUCAAAGCCCAUUAAUGAUUCAGAAUCAGUGCUUGACCUCCUGUAUUCUGAAUGGUGAACUCUGGAAGCAGGGAUUGUGUCUGGCUCUUUUUAGAGCUGGAAAUGUAGUGGCUUUCAUUAAAUACUUGCUGUAAAGUCUUUCUAAGACCAAUUAUUAUCUUAGCAUGUUUCAGUAUCUUCUCUAUCAUAGGCCCUAAGUUCAUUGGGGGAAAAAAAAUAAGAAGAUUCAACAGAAUCAGCAUUUGAAGUGUACCAUUGGUAGUUGUUUAUGAAAUUACCAGAUAUUCAUAAAUGUGACAAAUGAACAGCAGGAUUAUGAAUUAUCAAAGGAAAAAGUAUUUGCUGAGGUGAAAAAAUCUGAUGUUUGAGGAAGUUUUUAUUUUUAUUUAUUUGUUUUGUUUUUUUUUUUUUGAGGCAGACUCUCUGUCGCCAGGCUUCUCCUGCCUCAGCCUCACGAGUAGCUGGGACUACAGGCAUGCACCACCACGCCCAGCUAAUUUUUGUAUUUUUAGCAGAGACAGGGAGGAAGUUUUUAUUUUUAUAAACAAAAUCUGAUGUUCAGAGGCCCCGUUUCUUACAAUAAAUGUUGAGUCUUAGUUAAGCAGGAAUUUAUGAACACCCAUUUCCUGACUUUUUGCUUUAAUUUAGAUUUUUCUCCAUCCUGUUUCUAGCACAAAAAUUUGCCUGCUGUGUUACAAAAAUAAAUUUAUGUUGUCCUGUGCCAUAAAGUGAUAUAUUUAAUAUUUUUAUUCUUUGGUUUUGAACAUUGUAAGUUCCUAAAAACAUUUUAUUAAACAAGUAGACAUUUUGUUAUUAAAAAAAUGUGAUCUGUAAUUUCUUUGUGCAGAAUGAUUUGAAGUAUUGUAUUCAGUUUACAUGCGUUAUUGGUUUAUAAUUAAUAUCUAAUGAAAAUACAUGUUGUUAUAUUGUAAACCAUAUUGUCUGUUCUUAUUAUUAGAGCUCUUAAUCAGCACACCUUUUGAGUCAGUAUAUAAUACAUGUAGUAAAGAAAAAAAGGGCAAAGAUGAUUAAUGACCAUAAGUCAGAGAAAUUAGUUUAUAGUCAUCUGCCACAGACAUAGUAGUGAUGUUUCGUCCAACAACAGACCGCAUAUAUGACCGUGGUCCCAUAUUACUAUAUUUUUACUGUGCUUUAUCUAUGUUUGGAUACACAAGUACUUACCAUCAUUUUACAGUUGUUUACAGUAUUAGGUACAGUAACAUGCUCUACAGGUUUGUAGCCUAGGAGCAAUAGGCCAUACCAAAUAGCCUAAGUUUGUAGUAGGUGACAUCAACUAGGUUUGUACAAGUACAUUCUGAUGUUCACAUAGUGACAAAAUUGCCUAAGGAAGCAUUUCUCAGAAUUUGUUCCUGUGAUUCAGUGAUACAUAACAGUACUUGCAAAUGCCUGUCCAUUUUACAGACGGAAAAAAAAAAAAAAAAAGUUGAGAAGAAAAUGGGGUUAUUGUAACUGGCUAGGUUGGUAGGUUCCAAACCUGGGUGAUAACAGAGUCGCCUAGGAAAUUAAAAAUACAGAUUUUUGGAAACCA